AAUAGCUUUGCGCAGUGGCAGUAUCAUAGCCAGUGAGGUUUAUCUGAAGCACGAUUAUUACUAAUUGAAAACAGAAUGUGCAUAAAUAACAAGUCAGUUAUUCCUCCAGGAAGAUCUCGCAAGAAAUCAAGGCUAGCCUUAUCUUUGAAGUAUCUCCACAAUCAUCUGUGGGGUACAUAAUCUACAGCCGGAGAUACUUAAGGCUUUUUAUUUUGUGCCUGGUAUAAGAUGGCAGAUGUGUUGCCACGGCCAGUAUAAUGAUGCCUCUAGGGAGCAACGGUAGCCAUCCAGGAGGUACAGGCUUGAUCAGACUUUGAUUCCAGUCAGUCUCAUCAGAGAAUGGUCUUUUCUCCAUUGUUAGUCACUGAGGUCAGUGAACGACUCAGACACUUCAAUCAACAGCCACAGUUUGUUUACCCUAUUUAUGGUCUCAAAGAUGGAUAACAUUACUCUUCCAGUCUGUAGUUUUCCAAGUGUCGAACCAAAAAGCUAGGCCAAUGGAAAUCACCCAAGAAUCAGUAAAAUUAUAACAAGAUUUAUCAAGGGGAAUAUUGGCCAAGACUAUGAGAACAGCCUUGAGUUCUGCCCACUGAGCCAAGUGGCCACAUUCAUUUUUGAUUUUGCAUGACUGGCACUUCAUAUGUACAGCUGCAGCAGUCCAGGGGACAUCACUGGGUUUCAGCCCAGCUGAACUAUUAUUGAACCAGGCCUAGGCAUUUAUGGGAACUGCUAAGCCAGCAAUGUGGUUCAGGCAAUAGAGUGCCUCCUUUUUACCUAAAGCUCAGAUGCUGCUGGGUUCAGGCCAGCUACGUUCUUGAAUAAACAUUUCUAUCCAACAAUUGAGGCUUGCUUGUCUUUUCCACCUUUUAACACAAUUGAGUCCAAGUUGACUUACCCCAAAAUAGAGACAUUAGGCCAGCCACAAGGCUUCUAUGCCUCAGAUAUUCAGUUUCAGCAAGAAUACAGUAAUUUACAAGAGCAUGUACCUGGUAUCUGCAUCUAAGAGACAAAGAUCUCCAAACCCCUUAGGGGUGCCUCUGGGUGAAGGCUGUCUCCUUUUGCCAGAGGAUCCAAUUGGUAAAAAUCAUCAGUCACAGUCAUUUAGCUCAAGGGGUCGUUAGGUUUGUGAGACACUAAAGGUACUAACACCUCUCUAUUUGUGGCUCUUUUGAAUUGGGAGAUCCCUUAUGAUAUUUAUGAACAUUCCUAGUACAGGCAUACAAUACCAAUUAUAUAUUCUGCGUGGAAGCUGCAAAAAUAGUACAUUAAAUUCUCCCAAAGAAAUUGACUCACAGCACCACUUUAGCUUCCCUUUCCAUGGUGAAUUCCAUCCAAACCCCAUAGUUGAAUUUGGAUGUCCCCUCUCCUAAGCAGGACCAGAUGGGCUGGUGGGCCCCGUAUCCAACAAAGCCUUAAACAUUUGAUUCCCUUGCCUCCCCAGCAUACUCAGACGUGUGUGUAUAACCUUCAGUUCCCCUUGAGGACAAGCUGGCCUCAGCCCUGCCCCUAAACAUCUUUUUCCUUAAAGCAGCUGAAAUUGGGGUAGCAUGGGAUGGAGGGGAUAUGGAGUGGGGAGAGAGAGGUUGCAGGGAGAAAGGGGUUCUAUGCCAUGAAAACAAGGCAUUGCUCUCACUUUUCAUUUCAAUCUAUGCAGCCACUAGACUUGUAGACUUCUUUGGGUCAGUUUCUCAUUCCCCAUGGGACACCUGCAUCUGAUUACAAGCCAAAUCCAGGGCAGUAAGAGCCUGACAACUAGUCAAUGCCUCAUCUAUGGUUUCCAACUGGAGCUUGUCUGUCUUAGGGACAUCUAUCCAAGAGGGACAAAGCUUCCAUACAGCAGCCAAUAUUCACUGCAAAAAUAUUCUUAGAUAUUUUAUUGUCUUCUCUGAAUGGAUCCAGGUUUGUCAUGAUAGAUUGCAGGAGAAGCUGAGCCUUUAGAUGGCCUUGCUCUUGACAUUCACCUUUAACAAGAAUUGCAUGCUUCUCUCAUUUUCCAAGCAAAUCAGACUAAGUUCUUAAAAUUGAUUUGGUUUCGGAAGUCACAUAUUUCUCGCCUUUCUCACUCAGCGAGGGUUUGCGAUUCUGGAACUGUUUUCUGAUAGGGAAAAACCUCUGCCUACACAGAGUGAAUCUUCAUAAUACUUUUAACAGUUGGGUCUACGAACAUCCAAAUUGUCAAGGAAGUCUCCUGUGCGAAACAGAGUUAACAGCUAGGGCACUAUAUCGGCAGCUGUCUUUGACCCUAUUUCCUAUUCUUUGGUCAGCAACCACCACCCCAGUUCCUUCUCAUUAAUAGGCAAUAAAGUGGAGAACCUUGUAUAACCUGGUUGACAUAUAGGUUAGUCAACAUCUUUGUUAUUGAUACCUAUGGAUUUUUUUCCAAAUUCUAUUAAUCAGCUUGUGAGACCUUCAUCCUUCCUCAUCCAGAAAGUCCUACCACUCACUGUUCCAGGUGCAUUGCCAAAUUGUCAAGAACUGUGAUGGAUCUCAGACUUUACACUACUGACAAGCUAACAAGUUAUCCUGGCUCCUGCUCUAAAUCAUAAAGUGAAAAUGAUUUCCACGCUUGGGUAAUUCCAUAGUUUCUACUUCAAAUCAGCAGUUUCCAAAAGUAUUUAUUCAGACUAAGAAUCAAGAAAAUAUUGUCAUAGUAAAAUAAUAUUUGUUAUAUAUGAUACAAUAUCAAAUCAGUGACAUUACUUUAGUGGAGAUUUUUAAAUUAUGUUGCUGAUUCAUUACUAUUAAGCAGAAUAGAAAAUAUUUAGAAGAAAAAAAACAGUAAAUUGAAGGAAUAACCUGAAGUUGAAUUUCUAUUUCAAAAAAUUUUCUCAUGUUAAAUAAACUUAUCUUAAAAUAAAUCUUCUUCAUUUCAGAGGUUUACUAAAAUGUUCUAUAAUUUUAUUUUACAGUCAGAGGAUGAUAGAAAAGAGAAUGGUGUGGAUAUUCUGGUACCACCGUCAUUCAUAAAAGGAAAAGAUAAUGAGAUCUAAAAAAAACUGUCAAAAUUUUCUUCCAUUCAUCAGUGCUGCAGAGCUAGAGAAGAAAUAGAGCUAUGCAGUAUAACUGCUGAUUAUUUUAUGAUUUCAUCACCAAAAGAACAGAAGAGAAAUUAAUGGGGAUACCAAAUAGGGAAAAUAUGCAUUUAUUAAGUCUCCUUACAUUUUAUUAUACUAUAUAAAUAUUUUUAAAUCAACAACUUCUGGUUAAGUCAAUAGACUAUCAACUAAAUUUGCUUUUUAUGUAUUCAAGGAUAAAAUAAUUAAGCAGAUUCUGCCAAACACUUGACAUGUUUCUGGUAUAAAGUAGAAUUUUAGUGCACAAUAUUUAAAAACCAUGUGGCAAGCACUUUUUAUAUGUAAUGCUUUGUUAAGAUACUAUCAGUGGGAACAGGGCAGUUUUUUCAGUAGAAUUUUUAUUGCCAUGCUAUUUUUAGUCAUUAAAGAUAGGUCCACAAGAUCUUAUUCCAAUCUGACAAUUGACAUCACAAUGUGAAUUAAAUCAGUUUAGUCAUUUUUAAAUGCAGCUGAAGGGGAACAGCUCUGGAUAUUUCAAACAUAUUACUGUUUCUCUUUCACAAAAUUUAAUUUGUUUCUUAACUGAACUAGAGCCUCUGGGCGUUUGUAGAGGGAAAAUAAAACCUCCAAGACUGUUUUAUUCUGUAUAAAAGCUGCUGUGCUCAGAAUGAACCCGGAAAGACAUUUAAAGGUGAACAAAUGACAUAGCCAAGCAUGCAUUUCUUAUGAUGCAGUAGAAACCGUAGUUGGCACAUUAACCAUCACUACCCCUGUAUGUGGUAUGUAUCCAGAUAAUUUCAUAUGUUGGAAAUGCUACCUAGGCAGCACUGGCGGUUCCUACCUGAGACAGCUAAUACAGGGUAUUAUCUGAGGCUGCCAACAUGGAUGAAAAUUAUACUUUGGAAAGUUUGCACUUAGUCACAAUGCAAAAUGAGGACAGAUUUAAACAUGACAUUUUGCCAGUCAGGAGACUUUCUAGAAGAUGAAAGACUGGUGAAAUAAAUCUCAAUGUUUUCAUAAAAAAAAAAAAAAGAGUAUGAGGCUUUCAGACUUUCACUCUUUGUGAGGCCUGUGAUUUGAUUUUCCAUACAUGGUGUAACAAAAUUUUCAGGAGGCAGUAAUACAAUUACUGGGAAAUGGGUUAACUGAAAUCCUCAUAGCCUUAUAUCUUUGAGGACUACUUCUUAUUCCAUGGGGUGUCCCAAGAUAUAACUUUUGACAUGAGUUUCCUAUGUUCAGCUACUUGAAGCACUCCAAAUAUUCAGAGACAAUUUUCAGCCUUACCAGAAAGAAUGGCUUGCUGAUAUUAAAAAUUAAAAACUUGAAAAUAGAGAGGAGAGAUAGAGUUCCCAGUAUUCCCAGACAGACUUGCAACAGGCAAAGGGGUUGUUUAUAGAAUCAUCUAACAAUAACAGCUGCUAUUUAUUGUGUGCUAUAUCCAGUGAUGUAUACACACACACACAAAUAGACUGAUAAUCUCUAAUUCUCAGCAGUUCCUAUUAUAACCCUUUUACAGAUAGGAAUAAUGAGGCUCAUUAAGACUUAGUAAUUUGCAGAAGACCAUCUAAUCAGUAAGGCAGAGAGCCUUGAACUGAGGAUAUGUCUAAAAUGAGGAACUGAAACAUCAAGUCCCUUCUGAGCUGACACCCCAACUUCCUGACAAUGCAAGAUCACUGACUAGCUCUUUAGCAGGAGUUACAUGGAGUCAAGAAAAGAAGUAUCUCCUCAUGUUUCAUCUUCUUACUCAGCCAGUCUGCCACAAAUUGAGGAGACUUCAGCGGAUGGCUGUGGAAUGAUUUUAAUUACCACCCUUACCUGCCAGUGACAAAAGUGGCAAGGACUGCUAGCUUCCAGGAACAGCCAUCGCAAUUGUGUUUGUGAAAAGUGAAGGGACUUUGCCAGGCAGUUUAAAUUGAAACAUGAUCAACUACCCACAGAGAGUUAGUCCUAGUGCCCGAGGGACCACUUAAAGUGGCCUAGCUAUAAGAAGACAUAUUCCUCCACACUAUGUCGACAUAUACUAACAGAGGUGCUGGUGUCUGUUUGGGGAGAAGUUUGCAGAAAGGGAGAAAUGCAUGUAAUCCAUUGGGACUGGUUCCACUUUCUGUAGAUGAUAGAAAUUGAAGAGAGAGAAGCAGAAAGCUAUUUUAUCCAUAUAUAAGUUUAAAAUUAUAGACUCAAGGAAAGACAGGCAUAGGGAGGGCUGAGUUGGGGAGGCAUGUGAAUGAAUGUGAAUUGGAGAAAGAGAAAAUGUGCAGAAGAGAGCUGGAAAAGUAUAAAAAUAGAAGCCUGCAGAAAAUUAUUUUGAUCACUAUAAAACAAAACUAACAGACUGAUAGACCUGGCUAAAAUCUAAGCAGUUCAUAAAUCUGAUACUGAAAGGACUGAAAGGACAUUUUCAAAAUACUACUUUGAUUCUCUAUUGCCUGCUGCAUGAAACUCAAACCCCUUAGCUUAACAUCAAAGAUCUUCCAGUGCUCUUGACAAUUACGCCAUUCUGUAUGCUGAAAAUUUCACUAGUAAGUUUUCUAAAUGGGCAGUGAGGUGACAGACUUGUGUUUUAGAAAUAUCACUGGUAGCAUUAUGGAUUAUUGAUGGAAUAAAAUAGGAACCAUGGACAGGGUGACUAUUUGGGAAACUAGUGCAGUGGCUUGGUCUCAAAGAUGAUGAGGAUAUGAACUAAAAUAGUGAAAGUGGACGUGGGAAUUGUGCUGGACUUGGAUUUCAAAAUGCCAACUAAAAUUUAUUAAAGUUUAUUCAAAUACAGAAUAUUUUGUCUCUAGGCUAUUUAUGUAGAACCUGGAGGCUCCACUUAAGAUGAAGACUUGGGAGGAGAAAGACAGACUUUUCUCUGCUGGCUGGCUCAUAGCCCCUAUAGAGUUGAUGAUGGCACUAGCCAUGUAGAUGAUAAGCUAGAUCUCAGCAGGUUUUCUGGUCUUAUACACAAGUGAGCAGAUAGUAGGUGGUCUACUUAUGAAAUUUCAAAGUGGAAGAAAUGUUUGAAGCUUCUCAGUCAUGGAUUCUAUUCCUCACUUGCAGUUUUAUCUACUCAAUUGGACAUAGGCAUAACACAUAAAAGGAUAGGCAGAAGCCUGGCUUAAGAGACCUAUUCUCCACCCAGGCAAAGGGCCUGUUUGACUCAUCUCUGUGGCCUUCCUUUCAACUUUUCUAUUAUUUCUCUCACUGCCUUAACAGGUAGUUUUGCUGAAUAUUGCAGAGAAUUAUUUUGAAAACCAUUUCAACCAAAAGUGUACAUGUCACUUUUAGCUAGUGAUCUUAUCUGUCUUUAUCUUAGACUCCUAAGAGAGGUGAAUUAUACACACACGCACACACACACACACACACAUUUUUUAUUUAUCUAUCAACCAUGCCAAAUGUGGUAACUUUAAAAAGCAUUUAUUAUUUCUAAUGACUUUUUGUGAUGACUUGACUCAGCUGAGUAGUUCUGCUCCUGUGAUGAUGGCUGGGUCUAUACUCAUUUGGGUACUUGACUGGGAUAGAAUGUCCAAGAUGGUUCAUUCAUAUGCCUGGCAAGUUGGUAUCAGCUCUCAGCUGGUAUCUCCACUGGGUCUAUUAACCAAUAUUCCUUUUUUCUCCUCCUUGUGGCUUUCUUAAAGCAUGACAUGUACGUUCCAAGAAGGAGUGUUUCAAAGGAUAAGUUCCAGUGUGCAAGCACUUAGCAAAUCUUCAAUUGCAUCUCUCUUAGCUCCAUGUCAUUGGUCAAGACUAGUCACAAGGCCAGUGCAGAUUAAGGGGAAAGGAAAUAAGCUCCAUCUCAUGACAUCAGGAAUAGCAUGAGCAUACGGGAAAAGGACACUGUUGGGGGCUAUCUUUGGAGAUGCCUUACUAAAUACACACACAACACUCAUUUGUAUGCAGUGUUAAAAUGUGCAUUUAAAAUGAAUACAAAAAUCCUUCCUGUGUUACAAUAUUCAUACAUAACAAUUCAUGCUCAGAAUAUUGUCCCCAUACUCAUCACGUAAAGGGAGAAACAUUAUAAAGUGUCGUGGGUAUUAAAGCGAGUGCCUCUGAUAAAUUGUGGAUUGUCCACAGACUCUUCUCUAUUGUAGGAAAUCAAGGAAUGAGCAACCAUUGAGAUAGGGGAGCAAGUGGUGGAGCUUUUGGGAGGGUUGCAAUGCUCAGCUCUGCAGGUUAUGCUCCGCAUAGCAUUGGCUUCAUUCUAAGACGCCAUCGUAUGAAUGACACCCUUCAGAGUUGUGCAGUGCAAAAACAUCCACCAUAUCCCUGGCUCUGUACUUUCUAAAUGGGGACACUGAGUAAAUAGCAAUGUAAAACCCAGGAGAAGUAAGCGUAGCAGAGAAGACAGUGAAUUCCACCUUGGACAUGCUGGAUUGGAGGGGCCUGUGCAACUUCCAGACUUAGGUAUGCGAUGGAUAGUAGGAAAUGUUGAUUUGGAGCUCAGUAAGGCCGGGGAAUCAAUGAAAUCAUCAAAGUAAAACAGGUUUGGGAAGAAGAGCCUGAAACAAUAACCCUGCAAUGUAUGCAACCGAAAAGUGAGAUCCAGUAGAGCAUUCUGAGAAAGAGCAGUCAGAAAGCCACAGCAACUUGACAUAUAUCUGCUGGAAUGAGACAGAGCAGUAAAAGCCAUUUCCUUAAAAUGAAUGCAAAGAUGUCUGCUUAACACAGGGUGAUUAACUUUCUAUUACUGUCUUUACACAAGCUCUCUGAGGGUCUCCCAGAGACAAGGUGUUAAUGAAUGGAAAAGCUGCUUUUUCCUUCUCACUUUCUCCCUGCUGUGGAGCAUCUAGGAUGACUUUAAAUAAUGAUAAGUUUGCCUUGUGUAGUGCUUUACAGUUUACAGAGCAUGUUCACUUACUUUAUCUAAUUUGUUCUCUGCUGCAACCCUCUGAAGUACGCAGGGCUGGUAUUAGUAUCUUCAUUUUACAGAUGAGCAAACUGAAGCCGAGAGAAGUGAUUAUUCCAGAGUGGAACUGUCCUCCGACUCCCAAUUCAGUUCUGUUUCCACUGAGCCGCUCAACUAUAUUAAAGAUCAAGUCCUUGCUUUUCAUUUGUCCAUGGAGAUACCUGUGUUAUCUAAAUUAGGAGUUUUCUGUCUUACAGUUAUCAGCCUUAGCAGAGAAGAUGUGGCAGAAGCUGGGACUCAAGGGUGGCUGACAUUGUCCUUCGGCAUUUUUAGUGACUGUAUUCCACUCCUUCUCUUUCUGGUGUACGGCUUUCAGAAUAUAGGUUAUUUUUUUCUCAAACAAUGAAGAAAGGUAAUUGGUGAUCUCUGCCUUGAGUAAUGCUAUUGAACAAAUCUUACAAGUAUGAAAUUUAACAUGCUUUUUUAUUGGUAGAAACAGCUCUCGUUAUCUUUUAAAUCCCAAAUUUAUGUGACUGUAAAUCAUCUUUUUUUAUAAUUUAUCAUUACUGUUUCCUUCAAAUUCCCACGUCUUUUGGCAAACCCCUUUUUCAGCACUCCCUUAUCAGAAUUUUAUUCUGAGAGCUUCCACUUCUUCACGCUGUAUUUCUAUGCAGUUUUCCUUUCUUGUCACGCAUACAACAGAUCUUUACUGGAUGCUUAUUAGGUGUGAGAAACCAUAUAAGUUUCUUGGGUUACGAUAGGGUUAUUAUCCAAAAAUAACCAGUGCUAAUAUUUGAUGAACAUUAUUUCACCUGUCUCCCUCCAUCUCUCUCAUACGUACACAUGUAUAUAUAAACAUAUUCUUAUGCUAUAUCUCAGUCCUUCCAUUUCUUUGUAACAUCUAAAUUAUUCAACAUAAUUAUUAACCUGAUAAACCAAUCUGUACAAAUAUAAUGGAAGAUCUAUAGAUGAUAUAGAUAUAGAUACAGACAGAUACAGAUGGUAGGAUGGAAAUAAUUUUGCAAAAGUGAGUUCAAAAAAUAAUGCUAUUUUUAUAUAUAAAAUAAAUAAGUAUUCUACCUGAAUUUAUUAGAAGUAAAGGAAACUGGAACAAAGGGUUAAGCAACUGAUGAACUUCAAAUAAAUUCCAACAAAAUAUAUUUCCCACAAGAGUCCUCUAAUAUUAAGGAAAGAAAACUGUAAAUAAUACUAAGAGGCCAGAGUCAUUAUAGUUGCUUUUGUUUUAGUCUUAACUACAUGUUUCUAUUUUUUAAAGUGCAGAUUGGCUAUGUGCUGUCAAAAGUGUGAAAUAGAGAGCCCUUACAUGUUCUCCUACCUAUCCACAACCAUAUUCCAGUCCUGUUACCUUAUUAUUUCUACAUGUUCAAUAUAUGUUAUAUUCAUAUUGUUUUUCUCUAGUCAUAGUUUCUGGCUGAGUCUCAACUGUUUAUUUUAAUGAAAGUAAUGUUCACCUACAAUCAUUUUACUAUGCCUUUCCAUUCCAGAAUAUUUUAUUUUAAUUCAUUUACUGAUUAUUUGGAUUAUGUCAAGACAGUCAAUGAAAGGAUAGUUGUUGUAAAAUGUGUUAAUUGCCAUGACUUUAGAAACACACAAAAUUAUGUGGUGCCAGGGACAUCUAAGAAUAAGUUGUAAUUAGAUAAAAUGAGAGAAUUGACAGAGGAGCUGACACAGUUCCAGAAGUUGUUCUCUUUAUGUCUCCACACUAAAAUACAUAGAGAUACAUAAAGAAGAUAUCCCUACUCCAUAUCUCAAUCCUUUCAUCUCUUUUUAAUGUCAAAAUUACUCAAGAUAAUGAGUAUUAAUAUGGUAAAUUAACCUGUGCAAGUAUAAUAGAAACUCAAUGAAAAGCAUUUAAGGACAUAUAGGACUUGGAUCCCAAAUUAUUGCAUGCCACUCAUACAUCUGUCCCCAUGCAUUACAAAGCUAAAUUCCAUGCUAAAAUCAGCCCACACAUUACAUGAGUACAGCCUCACUAAACAGAGUGUCACUUGGCAGCAUGCUGCUACAUUUUGACUCCACUAAUUAAGUGUGUUUUUGGAGAACCAUGCUAGCAUUCUCUGUGGGAAGCAUACUGGCAUUUUAAGGAUAAGAGGACAGAAAAGGUCUUAAGUGAAUCAAAGAAGUUAUGGAAAAUGUGGCUUUCACCAGAAAUAUGCAAUGAAACAUAGAGUUAUUUAAAGAAGGUUUCAGAUGUAAGUAUUACUGUCCUGCUACAAAAAGACUUUUUUUUUUUUUUUUUUGCUACCAUGCUGUGUGGCAUGAGCCAAUAAGUUCAGUUCCCUGUGGGUUCGAGCAGACAUCUAGGCCUAGAGCAUGCCUGCAGCAAGUUGAUGUACUAACAAAGAGAAAACCUAUUUAGGCUGACUCUUUAAAUGUCAGCCUGCUGCAAAUAGUCUUCAAUAAAUUUUAACAUCACCCUAGUAAAUAUAGUUCAUUAGUAUAGUGUAUUUGAUUCAAGAGUUUCAAUCAAUAUAUGUAUAAGAUCAGGGAAUAAGUAAGAUUUUUGAUUUCUUAUAUUUUGUUAUAAAUACAAAGUAAGCCCUACUUUUGAGAAAUGUGAAUAUUAAGUUGAAAUUCCCAAAGAGCUGAAAUAUGUUAUUCUUUAUUCUGUGUUUCUUGUUACUUAUUCAAUAAUUUAUUUCAAUAUUUUAUUUAAUGUUACUAUUAAAUUUUAUACUUAAUUAUUUAAAAAUUGAAACAGUAGAAAGAAAAAAUUAAUUAUAUUGCCAACUUGUAAGUAGAGAUUUUCUUCAUCAGUUAAAAUAUUCUAUGAUCAGUUGCACAAAAUUUGACUUAUACGUGAGUGGUACAACCAUUGAAUGGCAUAGUCUUUACUAAUACAUUUAUAUGAUAUUAUAAAUUAUACAAAGGUCGAAAUCUGUGAAAAGACAGCUAGAUGUGAUAUGAUUUAUAUUUAAACAAUACCAUACCAUGGUUUUCUUUCUUAGCCUAUAUUAUAACAAAUAACAAAUUAAGCUGUGAAUGCAACAGUAGGCAUAAUCAAAUGGUAUUGAAAUACAGCCAUGUACACCUAAGAUCUGCAAAGCCAUGGAUUUUGUGUGUGUGUGUGUUUUCUUUCUUUUUCUUUUUAUCAUUUAAAGCCAUGGAUUUUUAUUAAAUGAUUAUCUCACUAAAAUUUGUGAUUCAUUAGCAAUUUGGCUAGGAGGAUUCGCAGGUGAUACUUAUUAAACUACAUUAUUUUUCAUGGCUUUUAAUCAACAUGAAAAAGAGUGAAAGUCUUUUGAAAAAGCAGAGAAACCUCUGGUGAUAGUUAAGAGAGUGAUGUCAUUAAAAUGGAGAGCUAGAAAUAAAGUGGGUCACAAGAAAAUGAAUCAACUAGCAGAUAUAUACUAGUCAUUUGAGAAAUCUGGCUUAAAAAAGGAGAAAAUAAGACAAUAAUUAAUUGGAUAAGAAAAAGAAAGAAAAAAAGUUUAUCAUGAUGAAGGGUCUUACAAUGUUUGAGGAUAAAAGCCAAAAGCCAAUAAAAGAAGAUUUGGAACAUCAUGGAGAAGGAGGAGAUAAAAGUAAUAACAAAAAUAUAUUGUGAAUUAAUAAAAUUUCAGUUCAGUAAUUGCUUCCUUAGCUUUUCUCCAGUAAAGAGUUAAGGCCCCUAAGCUGGUAGAAAUAGGCUCUUAGAAAAAGGAAAGAAAAUAGUCAUAGAAGCAUGGGGAUCUUCAAUUAUCUUGUAUUCCUUUCUCCCUUCUCCCAUCAGACCCCAAUCAUAGAACAGGAAGAUAAAAAACAAGAAAGUACUGGGUGCUGACUUGCUCUAUUUGACUCACUUAUCUUGCUCAGGGGGCAAAAGGAGGGAAAUAAUAUUGGCACCACGUAAUUUAAUUUCAAUGUGAAGGCUAUCCAUAGAGAAGCUUUCAUUUUGAGGUGGCUUACUUGAAGGUUUUAGCCAUUCCACUGAGAAUAAUCAUGAAGCGAUACAGUAAUAUGAGGAGCAUAGCCUACCUGAUAGGUGGAGCUCUAAUCCUCACCAUCAUGCCAUCUGCCCUCUGUAUAUUCUUUUUGUCCCUGCCUGGACAGGCAUUCUUCCUUCUCUUAUGUACACUUUCCUCCCCUUAGGCUUCAACCUCAGCACACUUGUAGAUAAUACUAUCUGUACCAUCAUAUUAAGUGAAUUCUCAAACUUUAUUUUCCACACUAAUCACAUGCAGAGCUUGUAAGUCCCACAACCAAAGUUUCUGAUUCAAUAAAUCUGGUAUAGAGCCCAGAACUGUUCUUUUUAACAAGCACACUAGGUGAUUCUGAUGUGGAUGAUUUAAAAGCCACACUUUGAGAAAUAGUCUUAAAUGAUAUUGUGCAGGGAUGAAUUUACUAUAUGUGUGUAUAUUUCUUCUAAUACUGAUGGCUUUGAUUUUAUAUUUUAUGUGUAUGAUAACCCAAUCAACAUUUUUAUAGUAGUCUUGACCUAGCAGCAUGUAUUAGUCCAUUCUCACACUGCUAUAAAGAAAUACCCAAGACUGAGUAAUUUAUAAAGGAAGAGGUUUGAUUGACUCACAGCUCUGCAUGGCUGGGGAGGCCUCAGGAAACUUACAAUCAUGGCAGAAGGGGAAGAGGCACAUCUUACAUAAUGGCGGGCAAGAGAGAGGAGCAUUCGUGAAGGAGGAACUGUCAAACACUUAUAAAACCAUCAGAUCUCAUUAGAACUUACUCACUAUGACAAGAACAGCAUGAGGGAAACCACCCCCAUGAUCCAAUCACUUCCCACCUGGUCCCUCCUUCGACAAGUGGAGAUUAUGGGGAUUACAAUUCGAGAUGAGAUUUGGGUGAGGACACAGCCAAACCAUAUCACAGUAGGAUGGUUCAAGAGUUAAAAUUAGUGCUUCCUCAUUAGUGAGAAUGUACCCACUAUAUCUUAGAACCACUAUGAGUCUUUACAUGCUGGAUCCAAGACCACAGCUGGAGUCAAUGACAUUGGAAAAAAAGGAAGCAUACCUGGUCCCUUCAUUACUGAAGAAAGAAUAAGGAGCACAGUGUAGAUUUAAGUGUUCCAUGGUGCUGCAGAUAAAGGAGGUAGAUCUUUCCAGAUGUUCUUCAUUUUCUCAGUGAAGUGGAACAAUAAGGCCAACUGCUGAAGGUGAGAUUAGUACAGGAAGGGGGAGAGUAGAUUUGGAAAUCAGAAGGCAAAGGAGAAACACCGUGUGGAACUCAAUGAGGAUUUAAUGAGGUUAUUUCAUACUACUAUAAAGUAACUUCUCUCAGUGUGAAGAAUUUUUUAAAUCAAGAAUUCCUGAAUUUUCCAUGAUUUUAAAAAUUCUAUUAUUAUAUUUAUUGUUUUUAUCAAUUAAGACAAAAAUAUUGAAAAUAUGAGUAUUGGCAUGUUACAGUUACCAAAUAAGAGCUAUUAUUGUGUCUUGUAGUGCUAGGUGAGGAAACAUGACAAAAUAAGGAAUUCUAUUUCCAUUACACUUAUCUUUCCAAUACACUCCUAAUGGGACGAAAGAGAUAACACCCACUCUGCUCCUCUUAUUUGAAGACACUUUAUUUAGAUUGGUUUCAAAACUAUUGACCUAUUUUUGGCAAUUUUUAGAUUUAUACUAAGGUUUUGAUCAUUAAAAUAAAACUGAUAAAAAGCUGGUUACAAUGCUCAAUAAAAGAAGAUAAAGGUAAAAAAAGAAUUAUUUAACACUAGCAUUAUUUUCUAAUAAAGAUAAAGUCACCUAAUCAAAUAACUGUGCUUCUCUUUGUGUGAGUUAAAAUAAUGUUUUGUUUUAAAUUAAAACCUGGAAAUUCCAUGUCUGCAAAUUAAGCGGUAACAUCAGUCUUUUUCUACACAAUGAUGUAGCAUGUGUGUUUUAUUUCAUUCUGUAUAGAGUAAUGGAGUUUCUUCUGCUGUGGGGCUUGCAGAACCAGCCCACUACUUUAUAGUUACAUACAUUAUACUCUCAUGGCUCCCAGGUAAAUGCCUUACUGCAGAGUUCUGCCUCUGAUCCUGCAGAAUGAUAUAAGGAAAUUGUAUCAAAUUAUAUGUUUUAAAACAAUUUGGCCAACAUUUGAAAAGUUAUUCCAGAUAAUAUUACUAUAUUUGAAAUUGCUCUUAUUUCCUUUGGUUAGUAGGUUAAAAUCCCUGAGGACUUUUAUUUAUUUUUUAAGCAACAAAUCUUUCUUUCCAUAAAUUGAACUAAAAUGUUCUGCCAUUAUAAACUCUUGGACACAAGCUUUUUCUCAUAGACGCUAUUAAAAUCUUCAAUAACCAAUUUACUACCAACAAAAUUGGUUAGAUUGGCUACACAGAUGCAGAAGAGCUGACACCCAUUUGACUCUUAAAGGAGUCUCUAAUCUGCCUGAGGCAGGAUUGCUACCUCGCAAGUCAACUCAGGGAACUACUGGACUGAAGAAGAUGCUGCCUCUCUCUUGGAGGCAGUAUUAGUCACAGCAUAGUGACUAAUGACACCCUGAAACCUGACCACUCCGUGAAACUGACAUGCAAGCUGCUGCUAACACAGCUUACUUUUUUGAGAAUUUCUCUGGAUCUUGCCACCCACUCUAUUUCUUCAACUUUCUCAGUGUCUUCAUUGCCCUCCACCUGUUUAGAUGCACAGGGCCUUCAUCCACCCCCAUCCAUGCAUGCACCGGCCCCCUCUAGCUUUCCCUCUACUGCCAAGGCUGAGUUCCCUUCCUGUCUGACAUUAUGAAGACAUACAUUAUAUGACAGUUUCUACUAACUCUGGAAAAUGAGACAGGAUAUUGUUGCUGAGCACUCAAAUUCCAUGUACUACUUUCCACUUUGUAUGGAAGAUGUUUAUGUACCUGUCAUCUUUGUGGCUAUUGAGUAGGAUACCUGCCUCCUUUGAUGUACUGUGAGCUGUUCAUAGGCAGGGAACAUAUUUACUCUUCUUUGCAUGUCUAAAUCCCUGAUAUGCCUUCCAUUAUGUUUACUGAAAUAAUGAGCACCAAGGAAAUACUAUUCUCUCAAUUCUCAUUUCUAUUCUGACAGUGACUUCCUUUUUUUUUUUUUUUACCUUUUUAGAUCAUGUAAUCGCUAUCUCAUUUUAUUUUGCUAUAAAAUGGAAAAACGUUACUCUUCCUUACAAAACACAUAUUUCUGUGUGUUUUAUCAAAAUCUUUUAUAAGCACAACCAAUAAUUUCUGAGAAUUAAUGGAUUAAUGGUUAAAAAUAAGAACCCCAGCCCAAGAGGUAGAGCUUGCAGUGAGCCGAGAUUGCGCCACCGCACCCCAGCCUGGGCAACAGAGCAAGACUCCGUCUCAAAAAAAUAAAAAAUAAAAAAAAAGAACCCCAAAUUACACACCUAAUUCUAGUUCUAGUUCAUUAAUAGUGGCUGAUACUUAAUUCUUAUAAUCAGCUUCUCUAGUUAAUUCUCUAAUUAAUUAUAAUAGCUUUGUUAUUAUAUUAUAAAGAAAUGUUUCCAAAGUAUAUUGUUAACCAUAAUAAACUUUUUCUAUUAUUCUAUUAAUUUUGUUCUUUUACAAAAUUUUAUUUAUAGGUAAAGGAAAAGUAGGCUUAAGCCUACCUUAUCUAAACUUUCUGCAAAUGCUGAACUGGCUAAGUCUGCAACAACUAGAUCCUUCUAGAUUGUUUAUGUUACUAUUACCAAAGUGAAGUUAUAUUGUCUUAUAAGUUUAUACAAAUCAAAAUUAUUUUAAAACAAUUUGACUAAUAUUUGACAAGUUAUAACAGAUAAUAUUACUAUAUUUCAAAUGAUUCUGAUUUCCUUUGACUACUAGGUUAAAAUCCAUGAGGACUUUUACUCAUUUUUUUAGGCCAUACAUUUUUCUUCCUAUAAAGUGAACCAAAUUUUUGGUCAUUAUAAACCACUGGACACUUGGACACAAGGAUUUUCUCACUGAUGCUAUAUAAAAUCUUCAAUAACCAAUUUCUACCCACAAUAAAGCAGGUAAUAUUGUCACCAAAACAUUUAUUCUUCUGUACUGGAUACAUCUACAUGAUUUUCAUUUAGAAUUCUGAAACCGUCCCUCAAAUUUGACAGCAUAACUCAUGGGAACUUUAUAAUAUGGCAGGGGAACACGAACUGACUUAUUUUAACAGAAAUGUCCAAAUAUAUCUGCAGUAUGUGUGUGAGGCAUUUUAGAAGGCACCCUGUUGUGCUGUAUAAUAUUGGUGGCACAGUGCCAUGCUGUCAUAGACUUAAAAGGUUUGAGAAAUGCGGUUUCUAUACGAUAUUAUAAGACUCUCCAGAAUUGCUUCAGAGGCUCUCAAACAAUUUCAGAAUUCCCUCUUUAACUUUUAUUAAACUUAAAAUAGUACAAACAUCUCACUGACUCAAAAUAUGGUGAAAAAUUGUGCAUUUCUUAGAAAGCUACAGUCUCCUAAAAAAGUGGAAUCUGAACUGCUUCUCCAUUUUAGUGUUUAUAUGGUUUCAGAAAUUGUCUCUUUUCAUCUAUUAUUAACCAAAAGGUUUUGACCUUUCUUUACUUUUGUAACUUUUUCAUAAUCAACUGCCCUAAAUCCUCAAGAACUUUGCUCUUACCUUCCAUGACUUAGGGAAAGCUCUAACAACAAACAAACAUAUUAGCCUGUAUAGAAAUGGCUCCUUAUUUAUUUAAAAGCCCUACAAAUUUGAAUUUUCUUUCAGUCUUCUUUAAGCAUUUGGUUUGCUCCAUGGCAAAAUUCAGAUGAUUAGCACUUCUCUAUAUAUCUUAAUGGCUUCUCUUUCACCCUUGUUUCUCUCUGAUAUGUUUCAUCACUGAAAAAGUCACAUAAGUCAACAUUCAAACACCUGAACCGAAGAUAACGUACAGAGUGGGUUCUUCAAAAAAAAAAAAAUUCUUAAAUCUUUAAAAAAUUAUUUUCACUUUUGUUUCUACAUCUAAUAUCCUCAUCACUUUUUCUUAAAUGUUUAGUUUUGAUAUUUGAUGACAAAAUUAAGACACAAGCGCUGUUCUUUGUGUGACCUUGUGGGCAGAAGGGGCCAGUUCAGCCUGUGGAUGAUUGGCACUCCUUCACAGCAGGACUGUGGGCCUGGAGUCCAAUGCCCAGCUUUCUUACUGAUCCACCUCCCAGAAUUGGCAGGGGAGAAAAUCAGGAUAGUGUGGAGCGUUUUCUGGGAAGCUGGGUUUUUUUUUCAUUUGAAAAAGAGUUUUUUAUUCUAAAAUUAUGUCUUUCCUACUUUUCUAGAAUUCAAGUGUUUCCUUCAUAAAUUAUGCAGAUUGAGAUGGUGGUUAUAGGUUUUGUACAUUUUCUUGUCAUCCUGACUUGUUAAAAUAAAGACUUGGCAAGUCCAGAUGGGUGCCUCCAUUUUUGUUGUUGCUGUUGAUCCAAAGACCGUGGAGCACCUGAGUCCAAAAUCACACUGAGAUCUCACUCCAGUUCGGAUAUGCAGUCUUCCGAUUUAAACAGGUUGUCUUAUUCUCCCCAUAAGAAGCUAGAGAUAUCAUAAAAGAGAUUCUUACUUCUGUGCUGUGAAUGUCACAGCUAAUAGGAACACAAACAACUGUCUUUCUCUCAUUGAAUUAAUAUUUACUGAGUACCUACUAUGUACUAAGCAUUGGGGGUAUAAGUGGGGUGUUUUUUAAUUUUUUAAAUUUACUUUUUCACAUCAAGUCCCAGGGAAGAGCUCAUUGAGAAGUUACCAUCUGAGUGCAACAUGAAAGGGGUGAGGGGAACACCUGGUUUUCUGGGGAAAAGCAUUCAAGAUAGAGGAAAGAGCAUGUGCAAUGCCCUAAGGAGAGAAUAUACCUUCUCUGACUGAUGAAUGGCAAUGAAACCAGUUUGACCAGAAUAGAGUGAGCAAGGUGCCAAGGACAGGCGAAGGGUGUCCAAGAAGUAGAGAGAGAAUGACAUUGUAAGGACUCUUUCCUUUGCCCUGAGGGACAUGGAAAGCUAUUGGAGGAUUUUGAGUAGAGGUGUACCAGGAUAUGACUUUAAAUUAAACACGAUUAGUGUGACUGCUAUGAUAAGGACAGGCUGAGAGGGAUCUCGGGCCAAAACAAGAAGAGACCUUAAGAAACUACUGCAGUAACUGAGGAUACUCGAUACUCCAAGCUAUUAUGGAAAAAGCAGGACAAAAUGGUUGGCAUGUCAGCGCUAUAUGUGUGGAAAAUUUUAAUGAUGUCAGCUAUAGGCAACUUCUAGAAGAACUUGACAGAAGACAAGAGAAGAAGUUUGUAAUAGACUGUGAGAUAGAGAGACUUCAAAACAUAUUAGAACAGAUUGUAAGUGUUGGAAAGCAUGUUAAAGGCUACCAUUAUAUCAUUGCAAACUUGGGAUUCAAGGAUAUUUCUCUUGAGAGGUUUAUACAUGGUGGAGCCAAUGUUACUGGAUUCCAGUUGGUGGAUUUUAAUACACCUAUGGUAAUCAAACUAAUGGAUCGCUGGAAGAAACUAGAUCAGAGAGAGUAUCCAGGAUCUGAGACUCCUCCAAAGUACACCUCUGCUCUGACUUAUGAUGGAGUCCUUGUGAUGGCUGAAACUUUCCGAAGUCUUAGGAGGCAGAAAAUUGAUAUCUCAAGGAGAGGAAAUGCUGGGGAUUGUCUGGCAAAUCCUGCUGCUCCAUGGGGCCAGGGAAUUGACAUGGAGAGGACACUCAAACAGGUUCGAAUUCAAGGGCUGACAGGGAAUGUUCAGUUUGACCACUAUGGACGUAGAGUCAAUUACACAAUGGAUGUGUUUGAGCUGAAAAGCACAGGACCUAGAAAGGUUGGUUACUGGAAUGAUAUGGAUAAGUUAGUCUUGAUUCAAGAUGUACCAACUCUUGGCAAUGACACAGCUGCUAUUGAGAACAGAACAGUGGUUGUAACCACAAUUAUGGAAUCCCCAUAUGUUAUGUACAAGAAAAAUCAUGAAAUGUUUGAAGGAAAUGACAAGUAUGAAGGAUACUGUGUAGAUUUGGCAUCUGAAAUUGCAAAACAUAUUGGUAUCAAGUAUAAAAUUGCCAUUGUCCCUGAUGGAAAAUAUGGAGCAAGGGAUGCAGACACAAAAAUCUGGAAUGGGAUGGUAGGAGAACUUGUUUAUGGGAAAGCAGAGAUUGCUAUUGCCCCUCUGACAAUCACUUUGGUACGAGAGGAGGUCAUUGACUUUUCUAAGCCCUUCAUGAGUUUGGGCAUAUCUAUCAUGAUCAAAAAGCCUCAGAAAUCCAAACCAGGAGUGUUUUCCUUCUUGGAUCCUCUGGCCUAUGAGAUUUGGAUGUGCAUAGUCUUUGCCUACAUUGGUGUCAGCGUGGUCUUAUUCCUAGUUAGUAGAUUUAGUCCAUAUGAGUGGCACACAGAAGAGCCAGAGGACGGAAAGGAAGGACCCAGCGACCAGCCUCCCAAUGAGUUUGGCAUCUUUAACAGCCUCUGGUUUUCCCUGGGUGCUUUUAUGCAGCAAGGAUGUGACAUUUCACCCAGAUCCCUCUCAGGUCGAAUUGUUGGAGGUGUUUGGUGGUUCUUUACACUCAUCAUUAUAUCAUCUUAUACUGCUAACCUCGCUGCUUUCCUGACGGUUGAGCGAAUGGUCUCUCCCAUAGAAAGUGCAGAAGACCUGGCCAAACAAACAGAAAUUGCCUAUGGAACACUGGAUUCAGGAUCAACAAAAGAAUUCUUCAGAAGAUCAAAAAUAGCAGUGUAUGAAAAGAUGUGGACCUACAUGCGAUCAGCAGAGCCAUCAGUAUUCACUAGGACUACAGCUGAGGGAGUAGCUCGUGUCCGCAAAUCCAAGGGCAAAUUUGCCUUUCUCCUGGAGUCCACUAUGAAUGAAUACAUUGAGCAGCGAAAGCCAUGUGACACGAUGAAAGUGGGAGGAAAUCUGGAUUCCAAAGGCUAUGGAGUAGCAACGCCCAAGGGUUCCUCAUUAAGAACUCCUGUAAACCUUGCCGUUUUGAAACUCAGUGAGGCAGGCGUCUUAGACAAGCUGAAAAACAAAUGGUGGUACGAUAAAGGUGAAUGUGGACCCAAGGACUCUGGAAGCAAGGACAAGACGAGUGCCUUGAGCCUGAGCAAUGUAGCAGGCGUCUUCUACAUUCUGGUUGGCGGCUUGGGCUUGGCAAUGCUGGUGGCUUUGAUAGAGUUCUGUUACAAGUCCAGGGCAGAAGCGAAGAGAAUGAAGCUGACCUUUUCUGAAGCCAUAAGAAACAAAGCCAGAUUAUCCAUCACUGGGAGUGUGGGAGAGAAUGGCCGCGUCUUGACGCCUGACUGCCCAAAGGCUGUACACACUGGAACUGCAAUCAGACAAAGUUCAGGAUUGGCUGUCAUUGCAUCGGACCUACCAUAAAAACCAAAAAAAUAAUUGAGUGCCUUAAUUAAACUGUUGGUGACUGGUGGAAACGCAGCCCUGAGGGACACGCCACGCGCGGGUCUUUGCUAAACCAAUCCUUUGGCUGAGAGCGGGAAGUCCGUCCUAACGCGCUGGCCGGACAUCAGCAGCAGCAACGUGUGCAUGAGCUCAGCUCGGAAACCCAAACUCAGAUUUUAUAUCAGGAAAACUCACAAUUGAGGUUUUUUUCGGGGAGUGGGUGGGGGAGGGAUCUGGGAUGGGUGUAUUAACAGCAACAAAUUUCAUUCGAGUGGACUCAAAAACUAAUCAGACUUAUGAGUUAGCGCAUUAAACUGUGAAGUUCUUGCUCAGAAAGGCCUUUGUCUUCACCGGAAAGGAUAAAAUAGUUGUAGAAGUCCGUGAACAUGCUAACCUGUGUCUCCAGAACAUCCAUAUAGUCCAUGGAAGAAAAUCCAGCUGAGAAAACAAAUCACUAAACUGUGAUAAGAAAAUAAUGAACAAACAUGUAAAACCUGUGGGAAAAAAAAAUAAAGGAAGUAUGUACACUUACUUUGGAGAAAACAAAUACUGAAACAUGCUUGCUUUUUAACUGACGUAAAUUCAGUAGAGGACAACACAAUUCUUUUUUCUAACCAUCUUAGGGAACAAUACAUUGCAAUAAUUGAUAUAAAUGCCAUCACUGUAAUAAACUUUAGAGACUUUUUUUUAUAAAAGUUGUUGGUCAUCUUCUUGUUUGCUGUAACCUUCACUAUGUCACAUGAGUCGAUUCACCGAUUGCAUUUGUCUCACAACCAGGAAGAAAAGCAAAAGGAAGAAAACGUUUAGGUUCAAUCAUCAGUCUGCGGUGUAGACUCGAAAGAGAUGACAGGUCACUCAUGUUAAUGGUAUUAUUUAUAAUCUCAUUCUGUGUACAACAUUGUGGUUUUUGUACCCACCAAAAAGAAUAAAACAGCAGAUGUUCUUACAAUAUCUACAGAGCUUAAAAGUUUUUUCUUAUCGUUAUAAAAGUUAUUUGAGAAAUUAUAAGACUAUAAGAGAGAUUGUAUUAGUGGUGGGCCAUAGUGGAAAAUGUAGCUAGCCCUCAUUAUUUUUUGCAUACUAAGCUACCCCUCCUUUUCAGAUCUUUGACUCAUUAACAGAUUAAACUGUCAAAGAUGGAGUCUUUGAGUUGGGGAAUGAAUCACUGUCCUAACAACAACAUACCUUGUAAUUGUGUGUUGAAAUUUUACUUGACUGUAUUUUGCUGCAUAAAAUUAUGUGUCUCUUGGGCUUCUUCCCUUAUUCCUAUUGUUCCCUUUAAAUCAUAUGAAGGCAUUCAUAAUAGCUUGGGGUAGAUAACAAAUGAAGAAUUAGUCUUUGUUUUCAACUGGAAAUUGUAAAGAAAAUUAUACUCAUGUUUAUUUAUAAAAAUCACCUUAUGUAUGAAUUAAACUAACAUGGUUCAAAAGAAGGUUUGGUUCAUUUGAAAUAAUAAAUAAGUACUCUAAUACAGAUAAAAAUCAUGUACUUAGGGUAUUGGCAGAAAGCACAAGUUAGGAUGAUUUCAGAAGUCUGGCCUUGAAGGAUGAGUUGAGUUUUAACAGGAGGAGAAGGUGUUAAGAGCCAUAUGAGUGAGCAGUGGCCCAAAGCCAUGCACAUCAGUGGCUCAUUUAAGGAAUGAAUGCCAUUAGAUGGGCUACUGAGAGUACAGGGAUAUUAUGGAAGAUAAAGUUGGAAAAGCUGAAGGAUUGAUUUUCUUCCAUCAACUCUCAAGAUCCCAUUCGCCAUUCAAUCUCUGUGCUGCAGUAAGAGCAAUCUUAAACAGUAUAAAUCACACACACACACACACACACACACACACACACACACAAGUCCCUCAGGAAAAAUUCCAAGCUCUUGAGAAGAUCACAUGAGCCCCUUCAUGACCUGGCGCUUGCUUAUUUCUUCCAGGACUUCUCUCACUUCUAUCCAGCUAUUCCCGUCAGCAAAUGAACCUCCAAAGCAGCACAUGGAGCACUGCAUAGACUAUUUCCUCAGUGCGUAACUCCUCCCUGUCUCCUCUUUACCUGAGUAACUUGUACUCAUCCUUCAAUACUCCAACUGAAUUUUACUUACCCUGAAAAGAUUUCCAUGGCUAUCCACCACCCCCCUGCCUGUGAGACUGAGUUAGGUGCCCUUUUUCAUGUCUUUCCCCCAUCACGGCACUUACCAUACUGCGUUGUAAUUGCCUGUGUACUCGUCUGUAUAACUACUAGACUGUAAGCUCCUUGAGGGCAGGGACUGUGUCUAUCUUGUUCACAGUUGUAUCCCCAGCACCCAGCACAGUGCCUGGCAUAUUGUAGGUGCUUAAUAAAUAUUUGUUGAAUGAA